GCAGGACCGACCUCCCUUGCCAUGAUAACCACCUUCGCAGCCGGCUCCCAGACCGUUGGCACCGAUUGCCUAGAAAAUAGGGGGUCUCAGGAGCUCCGUUUUAGCGUUUAUAUAUCCCAAUUCCAAUUAAGCCACUUCCAGUAUUUUUUGGCCAUUGUCAGUGUACAAGUCUUCCUCCUCUUCGAGACCAUGUUAUUGCAAUAGCAGCAAACGUGUUGGGAGGCCUCACAAUUCAUCAUGGUUUUUCUGGCCUCUGGCAGAUAGCUCCUUCCUAGCGAGCUGUGGAGCUUAAAGUCUUUUGGACACUUGAUUCUAUUCAAUCCAGUAUCAGACCAGGUCAUUGCUAGGAAGAACUCUGGGUACAAUAAUGAAUACAAUGUAUGUGAUGAUGGCUCAGAUCUUAAGAUCUCACCUGAUAAAGGCUACAGUGAUUCCUAAUCGAGUGAAAAUGCUUCCAUAUUUUGGUAUCAUUAGAAAUAGAAUGAUGUCAACCCAUAAAUCCAAAAAGAAGAUCAGAGAAUAUUAUAGACUGCUGAACGUGGAGGAAGGAUGCUCUGCAGAUGAAGUCAGGGAAUCUUUUCAUAAGCUUGCCAAGCAAUAUCAUCCUGACAGUGGCUCUAAUACUGCUGAUUCUGCAACAUUUAUAAGGAUUGAAAAAGCUUAUAGAAAGGUGCUCUCCCAUGUGAUAGAACAAACAAAUGCCAGUCAGAGUAAAGGUGAAGAAGAAGAAGAUGUAGAAAAAUUCAAAUAUAAAACACCCCAACACCGACAUUAUUUAAGUUUUGAAGGUAUUGGUUUUGGGACUCCAACUCAACGAGAGAAGCAUUAUAGGCAAUUUAGGGCAGACCGUGCUGCUGAACAAGUGAUGGAAUAUCAAAAGCAGAAACUACAAAGCCAGUAUUUUCCUGAUAGUGUAAUUGUUAAAAAUAUAAGACAGAGCAAACAGCAAAAGAUAACGCAAGCUAUAGAACGUUUAGUGGAGGACCUCAUUCAAGAAUCCAUGGCAAAAGGAGACUUUGACAAUCUCAGUGGGAAAGGAAAACCUCUGAAAAAGUUUUCUGACUGUUCUUACAUUGAUCCCAUGACUCACAACCUGAACCGAAUACUGAUCGAUAAUGGAUACCAACCAGAAUGGAUCCUUAAGCAAAAGGAAAUAAGCGAUACUAUUGAGCAACUCAGAGAGGCAAUUUUAGUGUCUAGGAAAAAACUUGGGAAUCCAAUGACACCAACUGAAAAGAAACAGUGGAACCAUGUUUGUGAGCAGUUUCAAGAAAACAUCAGAAAAUUAAACAAGCGAAUUAAUGAUUUUAAUUUAAUUGUUCCCAUCCUGACCAGGCAAAAAGUCCAUUUUGAUGCUCAGAAAGAAAUUGUCAGAGCCCAGAAAAUAUACGAGACCCUUAUAAAAACAAAAGAAGUCACAGAUAGAAACCCAAAUAACCUUGAUCAAGGAGAAGGAGAGAAAACACCUGAAAUCAAGAAAGGUUUUUUAAACUGGAUGAAUCUGUGGAAAUUUAUUAAAAUACGAUCAUUUUGAUGUUUACUAUCAUAAAUCAUUCUUAGUUCCACUGACACUUUACAUGGAAAAUGAGAUUUAUUGCUAUAAUACAAGAAUUUAAGAAUUGUGCCAUUGUACUUAUCACAAAACUAAUCACAUAGCCAAUGAUGUGUGAGUGAGAAACCUAUCAGGUUUGUCCUGAGGAUAUAGC